CCUGUCCCAUGACCAGGGCCAGCUCACCAAGGAGCUGCAGCAGCAUGUAAAGUCAGUGACAUGCCCAUGCGAGUACCUGAGGAAGAUGAUCCUACACCUGCCACCUCCGAUGGAUCCACUGCCUCUGUGCCUGACUGUACUGCUGAUGCUCCAGUGGAUAACUCAGCAUCCCAGCCUAGGCCCAAUGCCACUGAAGAUGGACCUGCACCCUGGGGACCCAGGAGUCCUACCACUCAGCUAUCCCCAGGAGUGCCCAGACCCUCAUUCUUAUCCAGGACCUAGGAGCCCUACCUUCUGGCCUUCCCUCAUCAGCCGUAAAUGAUGAUUUACUGCUGUUACCAUCAUCACUGCCUUCAGUGACCAAGGGCCUUCCAAGGUGCCAGCUCUGGAACGAAAGAUGCCCUUGGGAGGUGAUGACACUCAGGUUGAUGGACGGAUGGCUACAUGGAUGUGAUGGAGAUGGUUUACUAUCGGGACCUUCCGCAUCCUGCUGAUGUUUUGUUGCUUAGGAUAUGAAUGGCUGAGCGGAGGCUGUAAAACCUGGCACUCUGCUUGGGUAUGAGGUUCUUCCUGCCAUCCUGCCAUCAUUUGUUUUUUAUGUUUUGUCGCCAAAAGUGACCUUGAGGAACCCUGGGAGCUCAGGAAGGAAGGAGCGCCCAGAAGCAGGGACAGGGAGCUGGUUGGGGAGGACCAGAAAUCAGGUUUGUGAAGGUUCCAGAGAGGACCUGUCCUUGCGAGGAGUGUGGGAGACUGAGAUGGGGGAGGGGUCAUUGGAAUGAUGCGGGCGCUACUUGGCAUUGUCCAUUGUGAGGCACCACCGGGGUCAUCAGGGAUUGGUGGAGAGGGAGUAUAAAGCCCCAGGUUUGCUAAGGGAGGGCCCAGACCGAAGAAGGUUUGGCAGAUAGCAGAACCUUUUUGUCUCCCUCUCAUUGCUCCUAAGCCUCACGCUCCCUUGUCCCGCGUGUCCUGUUGCUUCCCUGAUCUUCUCCGUGACCUGUAGCUAAACCUUCCACCAGCGCUUGAGAACUUAAUUUGAACCGGAUCCUUUCCCAGACCCCUUUCUUCUUCUCCUCCUCCUCCUCCACCUCCUCCAGGGCGCCCUGAAAGGACCAGGACAUGCGGCUGCGCUUUUGGCUCCUCAUUUGGCUCCUGCUGGGAUUUAUCAGCCAUCAGCCCACCCCUGUUAUCAAUAGUCUGGCUGUCUAUCGUCAUCGUGAGACUGACUUUGGUGUAGGAGUUCGAGACCACCCUGGCCAACAUGGCAAAACCCCAUCUCCACAAAAAUUGGAUAAUUUGAUAAUUAUCAUUAUUGGGUUUCUGAGAUGUUACACAUUUAACAUUCUCUUCUGCACAAGUUGCCUUUGUGUGUCUUUCCUGAAGACUAUCUUCUGGUCUCGAAAUGGACAUGAUGGAUCCAUGGAUGUACAGCAGAGAGCCUGGAGGUCCAACCGCAGUAGACAGAAAGGGCUGAGGUCCAUUUGUAUGCACACAAAGAAAAGAGUUUCUUCCUUUCGAGGAAAUAAAAUUGGCCUGAAAGACGUCAUUACUCUACGGAGGCAUGUGGAAACAAAAGUUAGAGCUAAAAUCCGUAAGAGGAAGGUGACAACGAAAAUCAACCGUCAUGACAAAAUCAAUGGAAAGAGGAAGACCGCCAGAAAACAGAAAAUGUUUCAACGUGCGCAAGAGUUGCGGCGGCGGGCAGAGGACUACCACAAAUGCAAAAUCCCCCCUUCUGCAAGAAAGCCUCUUUGCAACUGGGUAAGUUUGUUUGUUUUCCUUGCUUUUGAACAUAGUCUGCCAGGUCAGGACAUGGAUACAUUUUUCUCCCUACAGCUCUGUGCUCAAGCCCUGCAGAGGGAGAUGGCAGAGAGGAAGGCUGCCUACAGGCAUCACAGUCCCAUCCCUGUCAGAAUGGCGGCAGCGGAGCAUCGUCAUUCUUCAGGAUUGCCCUACUGGCUCUACCUCACAGCUGAAACUUUAAAAAACAGGAUGGGCCGCCAGCCACCUCCUCCAACUCAACAACAUUCUAUAACUGAUAACUCCCUGAGCCUCAAGACACCUCCUGAGUGUCUGCUCACUCCCCUUCCACCCUCAGUGGAUGAUAAUAUCAAGGAGUGUCCUCUUGCUCCUCUUCCACCCUCUCCUCUUCCACCCUCAGUGGAUGAUAAUCUGAAGGAAUGUCUCUUUGUCCCGCUUCCACCCUCUCCUCUUCCACCCUCAGUGGAUGAUAAUCUGAAGGAAUGUCUCUUUGUCCCGCUUCCACCCUCUCCUCUUCCACCCUCAGUGGAUGAUAAUCUCAAGACUCCUCCCUUAGCUACUCAGGAGGCCGAGGUGGAAAAACCACCCAAACCCAAGAGGUGGAGGGUGGAUGAGGUGGAACAAUCGCCCAAGCCCAAGAGGCAGAGGGAGGCCGAGGCACAACAAUUACCCAAACCCAAGAGGCGGAGGUUGAGUAAGCUGAGAACACGCCAUUGCACUCAAGCCUGGGCAAUAAGAAUAAAUCCGUAGGUCGAAAAAAAGAAAAAAAUCAAAAAACAAAACAAAACCCACGCUCCAAAAACAAACUAACGAAGAAUAAAUAAAUAAUAUAAAAAUAAAAUAAAUACUGCAGUCCUUAUGUUA